AGAAGCAAAAGAGCAGAGCUACCAUGUCCUCUUGGAGCAGACAGCGACCAAAAAGCCCAGGGGGCAUUCAACCCCAUGUUUCUAGAACUCUGUUCCUGCUGCUGCUGUUGGCAGCCUCAGCCUGGGGGGUCACCCUGAGCCCCAAAGACUGCCAGGUGUUCCGCUCAGACCAUGGCAGCUCCAUCUCCUGUCAACCACCUGCCGAAAUCCCCGGCUACCUGCCAGCCGACACCGUGCACCUGGCCGUGGAAUUCUUCAACCUGACCCACCUGCCAGCCAACCUCCUCCAGGGCGCCUCUAAGCUCCAAGAAUUGCACCUCUCCAGCAAUGGGCUGGAAAGCCUCUCGCCCGAAUUCCUGCGGCCAGUGCCGCAGCUGAGGGUGCUGGAUCUAACCCGAAACGCCCUGACCGGGCUGCCCCCGGGCCUCUUCCAGGCCUCAGCCACCCUGGACACCCUGGUAUUGAAAGAAAACCAGCUGGAGGUCCUGGAGGUCUCGUGGCUACACGGCCUGAAAGCUCUGGGGCAUCUGGACCUGUCUGGGAACCGCCUCCGGAAACUGCCCCCCGGGCUGCUGGCCAACUUCACCCUCCUGCGCACCCUUGACCUUGGGGAGAACCAGUUGGAGACCUUGCCACCUGACCUCCUGAGGGGUCCGCUGCAAUUAGAACGGCUACAUCUAGAAGGCAACAAAUUGCAAGUACUGGGAAAAGAUCUCCUCUUGCCGCAGCCGGACCUGCGCUACCUCUUCCUGAACGGCAACAAGCUGGCCAGGGUGGCAGCCGGUGCCUUCCAGGGCCUGCGGCAGCUGGACAUGCUGGACCUCUCCAAUAACUCACUGGCCAGCGUGCCCGAGGGGCUCUGGGCAUCCCUAGGGCAGCCAAACUGGGACAUGCGGGAUGGCUUCGACAUCUCCGGCAACCCCUGGAUCUGUGACCAGAACCUGAGCGACCUCUAUCGUUGGCUUCAGGCCCAAAAAGACAAGAUGUUUUCCCAGAAUGACACGCGCUGUGCUGGGCCUGAAGCCGUGAAGGGCCAGACGCUCCUGGCAGUGGCCAAGUCCCAGUGAGACCAGGGGCUUGGGUUGAGGGUGGGGGGUCUGGUAGAACACUGCAACCCGCUUAACAAAUAAUCCUGCCUUUGGCCGGGUGCGGGGGCUCACGCCUGUAAUCCCAGCACUUUGGGAGGCCCAGGUGGGCGGAUCACGAGGUCAGGAGAUCGAGACCAUCUUGGCUAACAUGGUGAAACCCUGUCUCUACUAAAAAUAUAAAAAAUUAGCCAGGCGUGGUGGUGGGCACCUGUAGUCCCAGCAACUCGGGAGGCUGAGGCAGGAGAAUGGCGUGAACUUGGGAGGCGGAGCUUGCGGUGAGCCAAGAUCGUGCCACUGCACUCUAGCCUGGGCGACAGAGCAAGACUGUCUCAAAAAAAUUAAAAUUAAAAUUAAAAACAAAUAAUCCUGCCUUUUACAGGUGAAACUCGGGGCUGUCCAUAGCGGCUGGGACCCCGUUUCAUCCAUCCAUGCUUCCUAGAACACACGAUGGGCUUUCCUUACCCAUGCCCAAGGUGUGCCCUCCGUCUGGAAUGCCGUUCCCUGUUUCCCAGAUCUCUUGAACUCUGGGUUCUCCCAGCCCCUUGUCCUUCCUUCCAGCUGAGCCCUGGCCACACUGGGGCUGCCUUUCUCUGACUCUGUCUUCCCCAAGUCAGGGGGCUCUCUGAGUGCAGGGUCUGAUGCUGAGUCCCACUUAGCUUGGGGUCAGAACCAAGGGGUUUAAUAAAUAACCCUUGAAAACUGGAUCGGAUGAAUUGGCUUUCAUUGUGUUCCUAGCAUCUUCUCAAAUCAACUUCCCAGGACUCCAGGGUGAAGGAGGAAAAGAGGCAUGGCCCAGGCCCUGGGGUGUGGGAUAUGGUCUCCCUAGGGGAUGACAGUUGGGAUCAAUGGCCUGUGACUUCUCCUCUCCCUUCCCCCAUCCUGGGACCUAACUGGAAAUAAAACCUUGACUGUUGCCCGGGUGUCAUUUUACCAGUGGAUUUCUGCCAGGGCUUGUGUCCUAGGAGAAGGUUUAAGUUAAACCAGAUUGCCCAGGUCUCCAAACGAUUUGUCAUGCUGACCUGAGAUCAUCGAAGGGGGCACCUGCCCCCGGGCAAGGUUGCAGGGGCAGGAUGGGGCUGAAGGGAUGAGCAGGGUCCCGGGCCCACCUGCUGAUACAGCAUUGGCCAUGUGGGGGCUGCAAUCGGAUUUGGAAGACCCUGGGGCUUGGGGGCAUGUCCAGUUUUCCCAGCUCCCUAAAAAAUGACCAUGCAGCCUGGCGCCGUGGCUCAUGCCUGUAAUCCAAACACUUUGGGAGGCUGAGGCAGGCAGAUCACCGGAGGUCAGGAGUUCGAGACCAGACUGGCCAACAUGGCAAAACCCUGUCUCUACUAAAAAUACAAAAAUUAGCCAGGCACAGUGGCACGUGCCUGUAAUACCAGCUACUUGGGAGGGUCAGGCAGGAGAAUCACUUGAACCUGGGAGGCGGAGGUUGCAGUGAGCCAAGAUCACGCCACUGCACUCCAGGCUGGGCGACAGAGUGAAACUGUGUCUCAAAAAUAAAAAUAAAAAUAAAAAGA